CUUCUGGGAAGGGAGAAUGGCGGCGCCCGGGCUGCGGCUGGGAGCGGGAAGACUCUUUGAAAUGCCUGCGGUGCUAGAGCGACUGAGCCGCUAUAAUAGCACGUCCCAAGCUUUUGCUGAGGUGCUGCGGCUGCCGAAGCAGCAGCUGAGGAAGCUGCUGUACCCGCUGCAGGAAGUAGAGCGGUUCCUCGCCCCCUACGGGAGGCAAGACCUUCACCUGCGUAUCUUUGACCCAAGCCCGGAGGACAUAGCCAGGGCGGACAACAUCUUCACGGCCACUGAACGGAACCGCAUCGACUACGUCAGCUCCGCCGUCCGUAUCGACCACGCCCCGGACCUUCCGCGGCCAGAGGUGUGUUUUAUAGGCAGAAGCAAUGUUGGAAAAUCAUCUCUAAUCAAGGCUUUAUUUUCACUGGCCCCUGAGGUUGAAGUCAGAGUCUCCAAAAAACCAGGACACACAAAGAAAAUGAAUUUUUUCAAAGUUGGAAAACAUUUUACAGUGGUGGACAUGCCAGGUUAUGGCUUUAGAGCACCUGAAGAUUUUGUUGACAUGGUAGAGACCUAUCUAAAAGAACGAAGGAACUUGAAGAGAACAUUUUUAUUAGUGGAUAGCGUUGUUGGAAUUCAAAAAACAGACAAUAUUGCCAUAGAAAUGUGUGAAGAAUUUGCAUUACCUUAUGUGAUUGUAUUAACAAAAAUUGACAAAUCUUCCAAGGGACAUCUUUUAAAACAAGUGCUUCAGAUCCAGAAAUUUGUUAACAUGAAAACUCAAGGAUGUUUUCCUCAGUUGUUUCCUGUAAGUGCUGUGACCUUUUCUGGAAUCCACCUGUUGAGAUGCUUUAUAGCCAGUGUAACAGGAAGUCUUGACUAAUGGUUCCCGGUUUAGCUGAAGAUUCAAAAAAAAAAAAAAAAGCUUUAUGCUAACUGGAGUUAAAUACCUAGAAGAAUUUCAACAUUGUUUUAAAUGUUGUGCAUCUGUAACUUCAGGAGGAUCACUUGAGCUUUAAAACCUGUGCCUUCUCGAAACAAGAAUUUGUGCCUGAGGUGAAAAAAGUUUGUAAGUUAUUGAAUUAUGGUGUUCAUUAGAACAGCUACUAGCUGAUUCCCCUAUUUUAACAAACUGACAAGAGCACAUCCAUAAAAUGAAAACCUGUUACAACUAUGUACAGAAGGGUUUGACGUUUUAUUGGGCUUUUGUCUUUUAAAGAAUAUGUCUACUAUGGGUAUUUUUUUUUUAAAUGUUAAAAUGGGCUAGGUAAAAGGGGGCUGCUUUUCUGUUAAGCAUCGAUAGGUAAGUUGAUGGAUAAAAGUUACUAUGUAAGCCUAUUUUUUUGAGUCCUUAUUUGAAUAUUGAAAACAUUCUUGAUAAAAUGUGUUAGUCCAUGUUGGAAACAACCGAAAGAACAGAAUUCAAGUUCUAGUUCUGAUGUUUAUUAUAUAUGUUGGAUCUUGGGCAACUUACUUGAUUUCUCGGAAAUUCAUUUGUUACUGUAAACGUGAAAGCUAUUAAGAUUCAAAUGAAUGGUUUUACAGCAGGUAACAUGUGAGAAGACAGCUACAUAUUUGUAAAGCCAAACCAACAAAGAAAUAUAGCAAAAUUCACAGGUAGAUUUAUUACAAGAAAUGUCCUUUCAUGGGGGAAGUAACAUUUUCACUAGUGAAAAAGCAAAAAACAAAAAUAGCUUUAAGUGAGAAAACUAAUUUGUAAAGGGCAAGAGAAAAAAGCUGAUGGGACAGUUUAGACUGCUACAUUUAAGAUUCAGAAUGGAAAAAUAAAGCCUUUGAACUAAAGUUAAUAGAGAAGAUUUUUGUGAAGGUGCCACUAACCUAUUCAUGUAAGUGGCUUAGGUUUUCAAAGUGAAGCUUAAUAUUAAAAGGUUAUAGCUGUAUUGCUGGAUAACAAAUUAAAGCUAUAAACCAA